GACUUCUGCUUCCGGGUCGGAGCCAUGGCGGUGGCAAAUUCAAGUCCUGUUAACCCCGUGGUGUUCUUUGAUGUCAGUAUUGGCGGUCAGGAAGUUGGCCGCAUGAAGAUCGAGCUCUUUGCAGACGUUGUGCCUAAGACGGCCGAGAACUUUAGGCAGUUCUGCACCGGAGAAUUCAGGAAAGAUGGGGUUCCAAUAGGAUACAAAGGAAGCACCUUCCACAGGGUCAUAAAGGAUUUCAUGAUUCAGGGUGGAGAUUUUGUUAAUGGAGAUGGUACUGGAGUCGCCAGUAUUUACCGGGGGCCAUUUGCAGAUGAAAAUUUUAAACUUAGACACUCAGCUCCAGGCCUGCUUUCCAUGGCGAACAGUGGUCCAAGUACAAAUGGCUGUCAGUUCUUUAUCACCUGCUCUAAGUGCGAUUGGCUGGAUGGGAAGCAUGUGGUGUUUGGAAAAAUCAUCGAUGGACUUCUAGUGAUGAGAAAGAUUGAGAAUGUUCCCACAGGCCCCAACAAUAAGCCCAAGCUACCUGUGGUGAUCUCGCAGUGUGGGGAGAUGUAGUCCAGACAAAGACUGAAUCAGCUGCUGUGUCCCCAACACCUGGAAGAACUGAGCUUCUGGAAUCUAAUAGAUGCUAAAUAAAUAUUUGUUGCAUGAAUGAUAGUGGUAUGAGAGGAAGAGGGAAAAAAAACGGAAAAAGGCUUCUUGGAAGAGGUGACACUUGAGGUAAGUAUUGACAGGCUUUAAUAUGCCAGAUCAACAAGGUGGCGAGGGCUUUCUAGGAAGAGGGAACUGUGUUCUUAGGCCACAGUCUAUUAGAGAUGGGGGGACAAGGUAAAAGUUAUUUUGCAGAGAAGAUUCUUGGGAUGAAUCCCUUGCCCAUCACAUCACUUAAAGGCAGGCACUGGAGUUGUCUGUACUGUGCUCACCACGGACAGCUGGAUGGUGUGAGCUCCCAGGAUGGCAGGGAGACUAGUAAAGCUCUGCAGUGGUGCUCUCCCACUUUGGAACAGUCAUGAACUAUUGGUGCUUGUAGAGAGGUGGCUACAAGAAAAUUAUUUUUUGAGACAUAGUUUCAGUCUGUCACCCAGGCUGGAGUGCAGUGGCACAAUCUCAGCUCACUGUAACCUCCGCCUCCCGGGUUCAAGCGAUUCUCCCUCCUCAAACUCCCGAGUAGCUGGGAUUACAGGCACAUGCCACCAUGCCCAGAUCAUUUUUGUAUUUUUAGUAGAGAUGGGGUUUUGCCACGUUGGCCGGGCUGGUCUCGAACUCCUGACUUCAAGUGAUCCGCCUGCCUCGGCCUCCCAAAGUGCUGAGGCAUGAGCCACCGUGCCUGGCUGCAAACUAGUUUCUUAAACAGCUUAUCCUCAGGCUCACUGAGCACGAAGAGAGCUGAAUGAAGUAACUGGAUGAGUAAGUAAUGAUACUUUUUAAAGUAACAUUGAAAAGACAGAUGUUACACAAUUUGUAUUUUUGCUUGAGAAGCCAUCCCUUCAAAGCAGUUACAUAGUGAGGCUGUUCACUUAUUCGUAGAGGUGCUGCUGCAAUAUUUUCUAAGUGUCUUUGUAACUGGAGAAAAGCUCUCAAGCCUAUAGGGCAUGCUUUUAAAUGUCCUCAGUGUUGGCAGGACUGCCUUUUGGGGAAACAUUUUAACAUUCAAGUCAUCUGGAGCUGGAACACAUGAACAACAGCUGUGGAAUCCACCCACUCUCCAUACACAUUGCUGCUGAAAGCCUUUUUCACCUGGAUUACUGGCACAGCUGCCCAGAUGACCCUUCUGCUGCCAGUACCUUUUUCAAUUCAUGUUCUACACCAUGUCGCUCAUUUAACGAAUCUUUUAAGGUAUUAUGUGUCAGGCACUAAGAUGCCCAAGGAAGUCACAGUCUGGUGGGGAACAUUUAAUUAGAGCAAUACAGUGUGUUAAGAUGGGAGGGAUUCUUAACCUAGUAGCAUCUGAGCCAAGACCUAGAGGAUGAAGAAUUAAGCAGGCAAAGAGGAAGGAGGAAAGGAAGAGUGUUGUAUGUAGAAUUUUAUGUAAUACUCCAAACGUAACAGUGGCUAAAGGACUCCACUAGAUGACAGUCCUUUCUCUACGAUGUCCUCUGAAGCAUGUUUACUUGGCUGGAGAGUUGCAAGUGUCUAUUCUGUAGGGCCCUUGUAAUAUUUCACCAUCUCCCUUGUCAUCUGAUACACUGAAGCAACACUUUUAACCAAUUUCUAUUUUCAUAGAAUUCAGCUGUUUGCUACCUCUGCUCCUGCAGUAUCCUGCAGCCAGUAGUUACAAGCACCUGGAAGGUUGGACAGGGAAUACAAGAGAAGACUCUAAGACUUCUCUUAGAAGUCAUAGAGUCCAGUAAACCACAUUAUGGAAUCUGGACUACCCUAAGGGUAAUAGUAGUCACUGGAAGAUUUUAAGUAAGACAGUGUCAUGAUCAGAUAGAUGUUCUCAAAAGAACUUUCUGGCUGUUGUGGUGGGUAAUAUUAGAGUAAGAAAGAGGUAGAGAGGUGUGGUUAGUAGCCAACAGCACUGCUCUAUGCUAGGGGUCAGCCGACUACACUCCGUUUUUCUGUGGCUCAUGAGCUAAGAAUACAAAUGGUUUUUAAAAUGUUUAAAUAGUUGAAAAUAUGUAAAGAUUCGUGUCAUGUAAAAAUUAAGGCUGUUUUCAAGCUCCAAACCUGAGUAGUAAGUCAGAACCAUAUGGUCGGCCAAGCUUAUAUUAUUAACUAUUUGGCUCUCACAGAAAAAGGUUCCUACCCCUUGCUCUAAGCAAUUGGUGAUGAUGGCCUACAGUAGUGACAGUAGGAAUGAAAAGACUCUGAAUUGACAUUUAGAGGGUUUAGGACUGACUCAAGAACGCCUUUAGGAGGUGGAACUCACAGGCCUAGACGGCAUUGGUAGGGGUAAGGAAUACUGCAUUAGCCUCCUAACUGCUUUCUCUACUUCCAUUCCUUGCCCCUCUGCAACCCAUUCUCCACUCCGCAGCCAUUUUUAAAAAGAUGCCCCUCCCUACUUAUGACUCUAAAAUUGCUCUUCUCACUCUUCCCCUCAGGAUAUAUUUCCAAUUAAAUAUACCUAAGUGACUGCCCACCUCUGCAACCCAAUGUCACAUUCGAGUCUUACUGAACUACUUGACUGCAUUUCCCGAGAUCUCACCUCUUCUCGCCUGUACCCUGUGCGCGGAAAGUCAGCCCUCCACCUUCUCCCUGCUUCCACUCCCAAAAUACUUCGUGGUUUUGCAGCUCUGGAGUAUUUACCGUGUUGGCUGUUUAAAUUUCUGCCUCCAUCAGAAGGCAGAAACUGACUCGCGAACUAUUCCAUCCCCAGCCGAUAGUAGACGCUUAAAAAAGAACGAAAGAAGGUGGGUGGAGGACUUCAGUAACAUCAGGUGGCAGCCUCAAUUUUAUCGUUUGUGAAACGUGGAUAGUAAUCCCUCUAUCACGUGGCUGUUGCAGGAAUAAAGUGAAAAAACAAAACAGGCUAGCUUGUUCAAUAAAUGUGAGUUGAAUUAAA